AUGCGCCCAAGUUUCAACCUCUACGGUGGGAAAAAGACGCCUGCGAUAAAACAAAGCGCUCGGUGGUGGUGGCCCUCGCGUCGCACCUCACGCCGUGCAGCGACACGAGACGAACACAGGGUGCGCUCUGAAAGGCCGGGUCCCGCGUUCCGGUCGAUCGGUGUUCCCCGGGACCCGCUCCUCAGGGCUGACCCAACUUCCUCCGGAAGGGGCGCUCUGCCUCUAGUCGCUCGCCGGCUCCCAGCCCCGACCCCAGACCCCUCGGACGCCCCCAUAGGCCUAGCUGGCGCCCCAACCGCCCACCCUCCGCUACCCACCCGCGGCGGCCCCGACCCCAAGCCGGAGCCUACUAGUCCCAACGGCCCGCCGAGCACUGACCGGCUCGGGACAGCCCAGGCCCCUGUCGGCGAGCGCUGGACUCCUCAGCUUCGCUCUGCCACACCGCGCAGCCGCCGUCCGCGUCUUUUGUUGUCGCGAGUUCUCCUGGCAACCGGCGAAGCCCGCCUCCCGCCGCGUCCUCUCCUGGAUGCCGCGUCCUGGCCCCGCCCCCAUCCUGGCCACGCCUCCAAGCCCGCCGCGCAGGAGUCCUGCGUCCCCAGGAAGUCCGCAAAGGGCCGGCCCCUGGGCUUGCCUGCAAAUCCGAGUUGUGUCCCACCAACGCGCUGGGACCGGUCUGUGAGGCCUGAGCGCAAGCAUCUUUCUACGGGUCCACUGAAGAACUCUGCAUAUGUCCCAUGGGAGACCAGCUUUGGGCUGCUUGUCCUACAGAGAAAAACAUCCAUGCCCAGUCCACUUUACCAGAAAAGCAGUAACAAACAGAAGAUUACAGCUAGACCAAAUUAAAUAAAGAAAUAUGUGCCCUUUUCGCCUAAAUCAUCUUCCCUCACCCAUAUUUUGAGAAAAGCUGGAUCCAGGAAAGAAAGGAA